CUCCUCCCGGGGUUUGUAGCGGAGGAGGAGCGGGCGCCAUGGCGGUUCUACUGGAGACCACUUUAGGCGACGUCGUCAUCGACUUGUACACCGAAGAACGGCCGCGUGCCUGCUUGAAUUUCUUGAAACUGUGCAAAAUAAAAUAUUACAAUUAUUGCCUUAUUCACAAUGUACAGAGGGAUUUUAUCAUACAAACUGGCGAUCCUACAGGGACUGGCCGUGGAGGAGAGUCUAUCUUUGGCCAACUGUAUGGUGAUCAAGCAAGCUUUUUUGAGGCAGAAAAAGUCCCAAGAAUUAAGCACAAGAAGAAAGGCACAGUGUCCAUGGUGAAUAAUGGCAGUGAUCAACAUGGAUCUCAGUUUCUUAUCACCACAGGAGAAAAUCUAGAUUAUCUUGAUGGUGUCCAUACGGUGUUUGGUGAGGUGACAGAAGGCAUGGACAUAAUUAAGAAAAUUAAUGAGACCUUUGUUGACAAGGACUUUGUACCAUAUCAGGAUAUCAGGAUAAAUCAUACGGUGAUUUUAGAUGAUCCAUUUGAUGACCCUCCUGAUUUAUUAAUCCCUGAUCGAUCACCAGAACCUACAAGGGAACAAUUAGAUAGUGGUCGAAUAGGAGCAGAUGAAGAAAUUGAUGAUUUCAAAGGAAGAUCAGCUGAGGAAGUAGAAGAAAUAAAGGCAGAAAAAGAGGCUAAAACUCAGGCUAUACUUUUGGAGAUGGUGGGAGACCUACCUGAUGCAGAUAUUAAACCUCCAGAAAAUGUACUGUUUGUGUGUAAAUUGAACCCAGUGACCACAGAUGAGGAUCUGGAAAUAAUAUUCUCUAGAUUUGGGCCAAUAAGAAGUUGUGAAGUUAUCCGAGACUGGAAGACAGGAGAGUCCCUCUGUUACGCUUUUAUUGAAUUUGAAAAGGAAGAAGAUUGUGAGAAAGCAUUCUUCAAAAUGGACAAUGUGCUUAUAGAUGACAGAAGAAUACAUGUGGAUUUUAGCCAGUCGGUUGCAAAGGUUAAAUGGAAAGGAAAAGGUGGGAAAUACACCAAGAGUGAUUUCAAGGAGUAUGAAAAAGAACAGGAUAAACCACCUAAUUUGGUUCUGAAAGAUAAAGUAAAGCCCAAACAGGAUACAAAAUACGAUCUUAUAUUAGAUGAGCAGGCCGAAGACUCAAAAUCAAGUCACUCACACACAAGUAAAAAACACAAGAAGAAAACCCAUCACUGUUCUGAAGAGAAAGAAGAUGAGGACUACAUGCCAAUCAAAAAUACUAAUCAGGAUAUCUAUAGAGAAAUGGGGUUUGGUCACUAUGAAGAAGAAGAAAGCUGUUGGGAGAAACAAAAGAGUGAAAAGAGAGACCGAACUCAGAACCGAAGUCGUAGCCGAUCUCGAGAGAGGGAUGGCCAUUAUAGUAAUAGUCAUAAAUCAAAAUACCAAACAGAUCUUUAUGAAAGAGAAAGGAGUAAAAAGAGAGACCGAAGCAGAAGUCCAAAGAAGUCCAAAGAUAAAGAAAAAUCUAAGUAUAGAUGAAAGAUGAAGAGGCAGAAUUGAGAGGCUAACAUAUUUACUCUUGUCUAACUUAAGAGUGCCAGGAAAGCAGAUGCUUAGAUUUUGUGUCAAAGCUUGUUAUUUUUUUCAUACUAGGAUUAUGGUCUUUAGAUUAAUACUGAUUAUAUAGAGCACGGAAAGAUAAAGAAUUGAACAUUUUCUUUGUAUACUUUUUUACACUAAUUUUAUUGUUAUACAUAAAUGGUAGUCUUCAUUUUUGAAGUCUUACAUUUUCACUCUUUUUUUAAUGAAGUAUUUCAUACUACAAAAAUACAUAAACGUAUAUAUAAAGGGAUAAUAAAUGUAAAUAUCUGUGUACUCAUCAGCCAGCUUAAGAUACAGAUGUUGUCGACAUUUUAGAAGUUCCCUAAGGCCCUCUCCCUCUCAAAUAAUUAUUUGGAAUUUUGUGUUUGUCAUUUGUCUAUUAUAGUUUUACAACAUACGUAUGUAUCUGUAAGUGAAAUGUUAAUUUUGUAUGUUUCUGAAUUUUAUAUAAAUGGCAAAAUGUUUACUUCUGUGACUUUCUUUCAUUUUUAUUGCUAUAUAGUAUUAUAUAAAUAUACUACAACUUAUUCAUUCUUGAUGGACAUUUGAGUUUUGUUUAUUUGUUUUUGCUGUUGAAACAAUGCUGCUGUGAACAUUGUAUCUAGCAGUUAUAUUGCUUGAUAUAUUGAUAAAAUAAUGCCAAAUUUGUGUUCUGAAGUGACUGUACUAGUUUAUACCUCUCUUGGCACUGUGAGUUACCUUUGUUUCAUAGCAUCUCCAACACUUAAGUUCAGACUUAAAAAUUUGCCAACCUAGUGGAUGUUAAGUGGUAUCUACCUGUGAUUUCCAGCAAGAUUACUGUUAUCUCUGCUCUUCCAUGUGUAAGAUGUCAUUUUUUUCCUGGCUGCUUUUAAGGUUUUCUGUCACUGGUUGUAAGAAGUUUGAUUAUGAUGUG